GCUUCCAAACCCAGGGCUUGCGCUUGCCUUUGCCUCUUCCACAGUUUCUCCAAAAUAAAAAAAAAAAGAAAAGAAAAACAAAUGACAAGUUUGCAAGACUGAUAAAACAGGUUUCUAAAAUGCAGUUCUGGUUCAAGAGGUGGGCUUAGACAUUUCCACAGCUCUUGUGCUAGCCUGGAGAGGCAGAUGAAUACUCAACUUCUGUUUUUCAAUUUCUGGGGCGCCUUGACAGCUUGGGCGAUGCCCCCUUCUACCACCUUCAGAGUAACUGAAUAAGUGACGAAGGGGAAGACCCCAUCCCCUUCCAAAGACCCACCACUUCUCUUGCGGAAGUGGCCACACAUCAUUUUCCUCACUUAGGAAAAUACAAAAUGUUUCAAGAGCCCAUUGCUUCCAGGAAGUUCACAACUAAUGACAGACUGCCCCACUGAGAAGGGUCUAGCGGAGCACAGGUCACCAGCUGGGCAACAUUCAGAAAGUUAGUCUUCCUAUGCUCAUUUUCCUGGGCUGUUACAGAAGAAGACUGGAAGAGCGCGCAGGGACCAUGUCGGCGGAGACCGCGAGCGGCCCCACAGAGGACCAGGUGGAAAUCCUGGAGUACAACUUCAACAAGGUCGACAAGCACCCGGAUUCCACCACGCUGUGCCUCAUCGCGGCCGAGGCAGGCCUUUCCGAGGAGGAGACCCAGAAAUGGUUUAAGCAGCGCCUGGCAAAGUGGCGGCGCUCAGAAGGCCUGCCCUCAGAGUGCAGAUCCGUCACAGACUAAGGAGAUGGCAGGCAUUGACAGCUUCACUCCAUGAAGGCCAUCUCUGUUUCUCUCCUCCGCUUAACCAAGCUGUUGUGGUUUUUCAGCAUAGUGUUGUAUGUUCCAUUGCUAGCUGUCCUGCUGUUUAACACAGUGUUGUAUUUUUUUUCUAAAUGUACAUAAUUAGAAAAGAAAAUAACAAUAGGAAGCUAUGUGUAUCUUCUGUGUAAAGCAGUGGCUUCACUGGAAAAAUGGUGUGGCUAGCAUUUCCCUUUGAGUCAUGAUGACAGAUGGUGUGAAAACCAUCUAAGUUUGCUUUUGACCAUCACCUCCCAGUAGCAAUUUGCUUUCAUAAUCCAUUUAGCAAUCCAGGCCUCUGUUGAAAAGAUAAUAUGAGGGAGAAGGGAACACAUUUCCUUCUGAACUUACUUCCCUAAGUCACUUUCCUUAUGUAUCAUCUAAUACAAUGAUGGUUGAGUGAAAAUACAGAAGGGGUGUUUGAGUAUUCAGAUUUCAUAAAACACUUCCUUGGAAUAUAGCUGCAUUAACUUGGAAAGAAGCCUGUUGGGCCAGAAGACAGAAACUCCAACUGGCAAAAAAGCAAGCAUCUAAGAAAAAAAACCACCAAAGUUCUUGAAUUUACUAUAUUUAAAUGCAUUGGUUAAGUUUAUUUUGCUAAAUAAAGUGAACUGCUUUUUGUCUCUAAAAUGAUAUUCUAAAUAAAACCUUAACUUUUUGUUGAA